AUUCAUUGAACACAAUCUUUUACAACGCUCCGUUUACGUGCCCGAGUUUGCUCCUGACGCCCGCGUUUCAAUGUUUAAGUUCCUGACCACCACGGCUUUAAGAAUAUCCUUCAACCGGGAGGGAGAUCCAUUGCUUUAAGACUUGCCUGGGAACGGGGACGCCCCCUCUUGCAAUCUGUCAGUGCCUGCACCAACUUUAUCCUUUCUGGGGCAUUUUCUCACCAGACUGACAGUCCUUAAGACAAGUAUGCAGUUAAGCUGCUAAGGGAUGGAAGAAGCGAGCCUGUGCCUUGGAGUGUCUUCGGCGGAGCCGGAAGCUGAGCCCCACCUGAGUGGCCCCGUCCUCAACGGCCAGUAUGCCAUGAGUCAGAAGCUGCACCAGAUCACCUCCCAGCUCAGCCAUGCCUUCCCCGAGCUCCAUCCCCGGCCCAACCCCGAGGAGAAGCCCCCCGCAUCCCUGGAGGAGAAGGCCCACGUGCCCAUGAGCGGCCAGCCCAUGGGCAGUCAGAUGGCGCUCCUGGCCAACCAGCUGGGCCGGGAGGUGGACACCAGCCUCAACGGGAGGGUGGACUUGCAGCAGUUCCUCAACGGGCAGAACCUGGGCAUCAUGUCCCAGAUGAGCGACAUCGAGGACGACGCCCGCAAGAACCGCAAGUACCCGUGCCCACUCUGCGGCAAGCGCUUCCGCUUCAACAGCAUCCUCUCCCUGCACAUGCGCACGCACACGGGCGAGAAGCCCUUCAAGUGCCCGUACUGCGACCACAGGGCGGCGCAGAAGGGGAACCUCAAGAUUCACCUGCGGACCCACAAGCUGGGCAACCUGGGCAAGGGGCGUGGGCGUGUGCGCGAGGAGAACCGCCUGCUGCACGAGCUGGAGGAGCGCGCCAUCCUGCGGGACAAGCAGCUGAAAGGCAGCCUGCUGCAGCCCCGGCCGGACCUGAAGCCCCCGCCGCACGCCCAGCAGGCCCCGCUGGCCGCCUGCACCCUGGCCCUGCAGGCUAACCACAGCGUUCCCGACGUGGCCCACCCGGUGCCCUCGCCCAAGCCUGCCAGCGUGCAGGAGGACGCGGUGGCCCCGGCGGCGGGCUUCCGCUGUACCUUCUGCAAGGGCAAGUUCAAGAAGCGCGAGGAGCUGGACCGCCACAUCCGCAUCUUGCACAAGCCCUACAAGUGCACGUUGUGCGACUUCGCGGCUUCGCAGGAGGAGGAGCUCAUCAGCCACGUGGAGAAGGCACACAUCACGGCCGAGUCGGCCCAGGGCCAGGGCCCCAACGGCGGUGGCGAGCAGUCGGCCAACGAGUUCCGCUGCGAGGUGUGCGGUCAGGUGUUCAGCCAGGCGUGGUUCCUCAAGGGUCACAUGCGCAAGCACAAAGACUCCUUUGAGCACUGCUGCCAGAUCUGCGGCCGGCGCUUCAAGGAGCCCUGGUUCCUCAAGAACCACAUGAAGGUCCACCUCAACAAGCUGUCGGUGAAGAACAAGUCCCCCAGCGACCCCGAGGUGCCUGUGCCCAUGGGCGGCAUGUCCCAGGAGGCCCACGCCAACCUGUACUCCAGGUACCUCUCCUGCCUGCAGAGUGGCUUCAUGACCCCGGACAAAGCCGGCCUGAGCGAGCCCAGCCAGCUCUAUGGCAAGGGCGAGCUGCCCAUGAAGGAGAAGGAAGCGCUGGGGAAGCUGCUGUCUCCCAUCUCCAGCAUGGCCCACGGCGUCCCGGAGGGGGACAAGCACUCCCUCCUGGGAUGCCUCAAUCUCGUGCCGCCGCUGAAAUCCAGCUGCAUCGAGCGGCUGCAGGCGGCUGCCAAGGCUGCGGAGAUGGACCCCGUGAACAGCUACCAGGCUUGGCAGCUCAUGGCCAGGGGCAUGGCCAUGGAACAUGGCUUCUUGUCUAAAGAGCAUCCGCUGCAGCGCAACCACGAAGACACUUUGGCAAACGCCGGGGUUCUGUUUGAUAAGGAGAAGCGGGAGUACGUGUUAGUGGGAGCAGAUGGCUCCAAGCAGAAAAUGCCUGCUGAUUUGGUUCACAGCACUAAAGUGGGCAGCCAGAGAGACCUGCCAAGUAAGCUCGACCCUUUAGAAAGCAGUCGGGAUUUUUUGUCACACGGGCUGAACCAGACUCUCGAGUAUAACCUGCAGGGUCCUGGGAACAUGAAGGAGAAGCCCACCGAGUGCCCCGACUGCGGCCGGGUGUUCCGCACUUACCACCAGGUGGUCGUGCACUCCCGUGUCCACAAGCGGGACCGCAAGGGCGAGGAGGAUGGGCUGCACGUGGGCCUGGAUGAGCGGCGUGGCUCGGGCAGUGACCAGGAGUCCCAGUCGGUGAGCCGCUCCACCACGCCGGGCUCCUCUAACGUCACCGAGGAGAGCGGGGUCGGAGGCGGCCUCUCCCAGACCGGGAGUGCCCAGGAGGACAGCCCGCACCCCUCCUCGCCAUCCUCCUCAGACAUUGGCGAGGAGGCUGGGAGAUCUGCCGGCGUCCAGCAACCAGCGCUGCUUCGCGACAGAAGCCUGGGCUCGGCCAUGAAGGACUGCCCGUACUGUGGGAAAACUUUCCGGACAUCCCAUCACCUUAAGGUGCACCUGAGGAUACACACAGGUGAGAAACCCUACAAGUGUCCGCACUGUGACUAUGCCGGCACGCAGUCAGCAUCCUUAAAAUACCACUUAGAGCGACACCAUCGGGAGCGGCAGAACGGGGCUGGGCCGCUGUCUGGGCAACCCCCAAAUCAAGACCACAAGGAUGAGAUGUCAAGCAAAGCUUCUCUGUUCAUCAGGCCAGACAUCCUGAGGGGGGCCUUCAAGGGUCUCCCUGGAAUCGACUUCAGAGGAGGCCCUGCAUCUCAGCAGUGGACAUCAGGGGUUCUCUCCUCUGGAGAUCACUCGGGGCAGGCCACGGGCAUGUCUUCGGAGGUCCCCUCAGAUGCUCUGAAAGGCACUGACCUUCCUUCCAAAAGCACCCACUUCUCUGAGAUCGGAAGAGCUUAUCAAAGCAUUGUGAGCAACGGUGUGAAUUUCCAAGGGUCCUUGCAAGCUUUCAUGGACAGUUUUGUCCUCAGUUCCUUGAAGAAGGAGAAGGACAUGAAGGACAAAGCCCUGGCUGACCCCCCUUCCAUGAAAGUCCACGGAGUGGAUGGUGGUGAGGAGAAACCCAGUGGCAAGUCCUCCCAGAGGAAGUCCGAGAAAUCUCAGUAUGAACCCCUGGACUUGUCUGUGCGGCCAGAUGCCGCCUCCCUCCCGGGCUCCUCGGUAACUGUGCAGGACAGCAUUGCAUGGCACGGCUGCUUGUUUUGUGCUUUCACAACGUCCUCCAUGGAGCUCAUGGCCCUUCAUCUCCAGGCCAACCACCUGGGCAAAGCGAAACGCAAAGAUAACACCAUCGGGGUCACAGUCAACUGCAAAGACCAAGCCCGGGAGGCGAGUAAGAUGGCCCUGCUGCCCUCGUUACAAUCAAACAAAGACCUGGGCCUCUCCAAUAUGAUCAGCUCUCUAGACUCUGCUUCUGAGAAGAUGGCCCAAGGUCAGCUCAAGGAGACUCUGGGAGAGCAGAAGAGCGGUGCAUGGACCGGCCACGUGGACCCUGCAUUUUGUAACUUCCCAUCAGACUUCUACAAGCAGUUUGGUGUUUACCCAGGCAUGGUUGGCUCAGGGGCCUCCAGUUCCUGCCCCAACAAGGAGCCUGAUGGAAAGGCCCACUCUGAAGAGGAUGUCCCCAUCCUGAUCCCCGAAACCACGAGUAAGAACACUACUGAUGACCUCUCUGACAUUGCCUCCUCAGAGGACAUGGACUCCUCCAAGGGGGAGAACAACGAUGAAGAGGAUGUUGAAACCGAACCGGAAAUGAUGACCAAGCCACUGUCUGCCCUCAGCAAAGACAGCAGCAGCGAUGGCGGGGACAGCCUGCAGCCCACAGGCACCUCCCAGCCCGUCCAGGGACUGGUCUCACCUUUAUCCCAAGCACCGGAGAAGCAGUGGCACAGCCAGGGUCUUCUCCAAGCCCAGGACCCCUUGGCGGGCCUGCCAAAGCCGGAGCGGGGGCCCCAGAGCCUGGACAAGCCGAUGAACAUGCUGUCGGUCCUCAGGGCCUACAGUUCUGAUGGCUUAGCAGCCUUUAACGGACUUGCAAGUAGCACAGCAAAUUCUGGAUGUAUCAAGAGGCCAGACUUGUGUGGUAAGUUUUAGAAUCCUCUUCCUAUAGUUCAUUUCCCAAAACAUCAGUGCUGAAUUGUGCAUUUAAAAAAAUGAGGUAGACUUAUCCAUGAGCAACUUUUGAAUGAAAUAUUUGAAAAAACCCUCAAUGCUGUAUCUGCAAUGUAGACAAUCAUAAAAGUCCAUUUUGUUUAGAAGUUUUAGAACUCAUACUUUUGUGUUCUAAUUUGCAUUAUAAUGUACUAAAAUGCCUGUACAGAAGGCAUGGAAAAGGGGGUGGUCGCUCACCAUGUGAACUACUCCUGUUUGCCAUCUAGAACUUGAAGGGGGGAAAAUCGACUUACAAAACAAAAAUGAAAAGAGACAUGGUAACUUGCAAAUUCUUCAGUAUUUUCAAUUUAUGCAAAAGAUGCCUAAAGACAAUUCCUUACUGCUUUGCUAAGCCAAAUCUGCUUUCUUAAACUUUUCUUUUAUUGACUUAGAGGAUACUAAAAUCAUAUCACACUAACAACAGUAUGGAAAUAAAGCGACCUUCUCUCCAAAGAGGGAGAUGGUUUCUGGGUGUUUGUGACUCAUUUUUAGACAAACCAAAUGGCAGUUACUGUGACUUUGGCCUUCUGCGCUUGCCUUCUGUUUGUCUGUCUGUUCACCUGUCUGUCUGUUGCUCUAACAAGACAUGUACAUUGUGAAGUCCCUGAACAGUAGUGGUGUGACCCUGUGCAUCUUGGAUUCAUGCUUGUCUGAUCCUGUAGCAAACUGACACUUCUUUAUCUCCUUAAAGCAUAUGGGUACCCCAAAGGAAUUCCAGAUUUCCGAACAUCAUUGUAAGUUUAAGGACUAGGUUUGGAUCAAAUGAAUGUUUGGGUGGGCAGGGGGAAUCAAAGUCAUUGUCUUGGCACCCUGAUAUCUGUAUUUGGAAGCCUUUCUCCGAAAAGAAGCUCCAUGCAUUCUUCCCUUUGAAACCAGCUCCAAAUAUCCUCACCAGAGACAAAUGACCAUGAUACAUUUCCAACUGUAAUUUAUGAAUGGAUUUCUGUAAUUUUACUUCACCUGUGGAAGGAAGGCAGGAAGGCAGGAAGGCAGGAAGGGAGGAGGGCAGGAUGGAAAGAAGGAAGGAAGGAAGGGAAGGGAAGGAAAGAAAAGGGAAGGAAGGGGGGGAAAUAGAAGAGAGUAUUUUUGAACCUCAACAUCCUGUUGUUCGUUUAAGCACAGAGAAGAAUUCAGGAAGCUAGACUCUGGGUUCAUAAUUUAGAUUGAUAUAUUUCUUUUAUUCCUCUUCUUCCCUAAUUCACUAGGAACUGAAUCAAGCGGUCAGAAAUAUUUUUUUGAAUUGUCGAAAAUCACUAAAUGGAUUUCUGACAGCUCAAAAAAAUAUUGACAGUUCCUUAUGCUGAAUGAUUCACAAGGCCCCAUUAACCACUACCCCCAGAUCUAUUUUUAGCCACAUACAAUUCAUUACUUUUGAAGCUGUUAAAAACAAUAUUUAAAAGAAGGGAAAAAAGCGUUUUAUGUUAGUCCAAAUUUUUUCCCCUUUUUUUUUUAAACUGGGGGAGCAAUGUUGAAGGCUUUUUUUUCUUUUUUUCAUUGUUGUUUUAGGUUUGUGAUCGGGGUGGUUUCUUUUUUAUUGUUGUUUAGAGUCUUUUUUUUUUUUAAGUCUAUUUUCAGUUCUUUCAACUACCUACGUAGGACCAUAGUCCCUGCCAGGAAUCCAUGCAUCAGAAAAGAUCAAAACCUGGCAUGUUCAUGAGCUCAUUAUUAUUGAAAUGAGCUCAUAUUACCCCUAUUAAUUUUCCCAUCUUCCUAUCAGUAAUGAAGGAAGGCUGCCUGGCUCGAGGAAGUUUGCCCAGUGGUAUCCUUUCGCACCAGGCGAGGUUGAAUGGGAAGCCAACGUCAGGGAGCCUGCCGGGUCUUGAGAGCCUUUUAUCUCUGGGCUGCAAGCUCCUAGGAACUUCUCACCUUUUCCCAAAACAGCAGCACACGACACGUCCCUGACAUUUCCCCGCUAUGUGCAAACCGUGUUGCCCAGUCCACCCUUCAGCCUUUGGGCAGCAGAUCCUGGGAUGUAAGUUGUGCCCCCCACCCCUCGCCUCUUUCAUGGGGCUUGGGGACCCUCAUGUCAGCCAAGCUUGAAGGCUUCCUGGUUGCUUCUGCAGCAGAGGGUUCAGGCCCCUUGUUCCGCCUUCCACUCCUGGGAAGAUGCUGAAAUUGACUCUGGCCACGAGCUGCCUAUUUUUAGAGAGUGUGAGUUCUGCAUUCCAUUUGGCCCCAUUUCUUCUGUGUCCUCUUGCUUUAGUUUGGAAGUAGGCAGGAAAAGACCCUCCCUGGCUCUUGCAUUUGCUUGGGGGUGGGGCCACUGCCCUCUUGCCUCUAGGAUGGGCCUGACUCUGCCAGUUCUCAUCCCACUCCCCCCAUAUCUGGCCCACCAUAAUUGCAGUCCUCUUCUUAUUUUCUUGCGGGCUACUGUGAUAUCCCAGAAGGUCCAGACAUAUUCAUCCUUUCUAAAAGUUACAACCUAGGAGGAACACAAAUCCAAAUGGGCUGUUUUUUUUUUCUUAAAUAGUGUAAUUCACUCUCUUUUUAGCAUGGCAAGAAGCACAAGUGACAUUUGUAAGCUUCAAACCCCCACUAGCUUCCCUUUGCAAGGGUAGAAGUGAUAUUAGCACAAUGAAUAAAAUAUUUCUAAUGUUUAUUCCUCCUUCUCUUCUUCACUCAAAGUAGGUAUGGGUUUCUAAAUCCGCCUACCAGGCUGAUCACUAUUUCUCCUUAAGAAUCUGGGCUUUGUCAGACCAAAGCAUCAUUCCUAGAUUUCUCAUCUCAGAUGGAUAAAGUUGAGGGCUGGUUUUGUCUGGUUAGUAGACCUAAAUCCCCACUUUCAUGAUUAUAGAAACAGGCUUAUAGGAGGAGCUAAUGUUCCCAUGUUUCUUAAGGAAGGGCUCUGUUCUCAAGGGGUGUAAAAGUGUUUGAACAAGCAUCAGAAAUACCUAGUUCAAAUCAUAUAAACUCCCCACAGAUCUCAGCAGCUCCUCCAACCCUUGCUGUUGAUUUGGAGAAGGUGGCAUCUCACCCUAUUCUGUGGGUGAUACUCAUAUUGCAGGCUGUACUUUCAGGAUCUUCCAUCAUUUCUGCAUGCCUUCUUCCUAACUUUUAAAACUCUGGUCCUAAAUUCCUUGGUGCCAUAGAGCCAGGGUCCUGGCCAGUGUGCCCUGCCCAUCCUAACAGCCAAUGGAUUCCUAACUCUGGUGCAGAAGGAGAGCCACCGAGGGGAGAAGCCGACCCAGCCAGUUGGGUGGGGAGACGCCUGUUGCAUAUGACAGUGUCGAGAGCUUCAGUGGGAAUUUUCUAAAGCUCUUUCCACAGAGGACAGCACACGGCCUGUCAGAGACAUAUUACAAUAAUCCCAAGGAAGAGGUUAAGCCAUCUUGGAUUAAGCCAGAGGACAGGCAUCUUUGCUUCCACAGUGGGUCAGAUCCCACUAGGGGUCUGAUCUCAUUAUAGGAAAUCCCACUCCAAUCAAAUCCUUAGUUUCUUGAGGUGACUUCCAGUCUCCAGGCAUGGGUCACAUGUCUUUAUUCUGUCAAAGAGCAUAAUGUACAAGGGUACUCCAGUGCCAUCGGAGAAUUUGGAUAUGCCCUUGGUUUUAUUGGAAUGUUUGACCUUGGUUUUGUAAUGGGAUAGACUCCACAUGAGUAUUUAAAGGUGGAGAGGGGAAGACCAGAGCAGUGUUUGCAUCCAUGGACAAAGCAAGGCAGAUAAGCCCAGUCUAGUCUGAGAAAUGCUAAUGCACUGUUGGGUCGGCACUUGGCUGGGAAGGGGCAGGCUUCCCUGUGCACACAGCACCAAGGCUGGUCUGCACAGCACCCAUGGGGCCCACUGCAUGGAACGGUUAAAAAGUGUGUUUCAUCUGGGAGUUUGUGGAUUUGGACAGCAACCAGAUCACCCUUACUCCUUGCCUUUCAAACCUAAGAGAGAUGGCCAGGGUGUGGAGUUGUUGUGUGCCAGGUCUCCCAGUCAGGCUUUGCACUGUGUCCUUUGGUGGACCCAGGGGUAGGCAGGACAGAGAAGAAUGAAUGACAGAUGAACGGGAAAGCAGGGAAAAGAGCACACUCCCCUUUGCCCCAAGGAGCUCUGCUCUGUAGUGACUGCCACUCAGGGAAGGCUGGCUGAACUGGUAGCAUCUGUAAGCAGGCUGAGGGCAGGCACUGCGGCUCACACCUGUAAUCCCAGCACUCUGGGAGGCUGAGGCAGGGGCGUUGCAUAAGCCCAGGAGUUCAAGGCCACUGUGAGCUAGGAUCAUGACAUUGCACUCGAGCCUGGGUGACAGAGUGAAACCCCUUCUGUAAAAUAAACAUGAAAUAAAUAUCAGCAAGUUGAUUGUGGGCACGAGGCCCUAUGUGCAGUGGCUACCAGACCUAGUGACCCAGUGGGCCUGGGAGGAAGUGAGGGAGAAUGCAAGCCCAUUAACAGCAGUCAUCCUAACAUCCCCAGCUUAUCAUCCUCAGGUUAUUGGGCAACUGGCUUCCCCAACCCAAAUUAUACCUGAGACUAUGGAAUAAAGGUCUUCUGGGCUUCCACAUUAGUGAAAUAAUUGGGACCCCCCCCCCUCCCAAGAAUUCGGGUCCAUUGAAACCUAUUCAAAUUACAUAUUUUUAUGUGUGAUGAGAUGAACCAGGACAACCAAAGCUGAACUCUCUUAAAAUGUGACUUAUCUUUUCCCUAAGCCUUAUAGAUUUCUUGGCAUAGGCAGUCGGAGAAUACCUACUUUUUUUUUUUUUUUUUUUUUUUUGGAGAUGGAGUUUUGCUCUGUUGCCUGGGCUGGAGUGCAGUGUGCGAUCUCGGCUCACGGCAACUUCCGUCUCCUGGGUUCAAGCGAUUCUCCUGCCUGUCUCCCAAGUAGCUGGGAUUACAGGUGCACGCCACCACACCUGGCUAAUUUUGUAUUUUUAGUAGAGACAGGGUUUCAUCAUGUUGGUCAGGCUGGUCUUGAACUUCUGACCUCAGGUGAUCCGCCCACCUCAGCCUCCCAAAGUGCUGGGAUUAUAGGCAUGAGCCACCGCGCCUGGCCAAUACCUACCCUUUUACGAGCUACUCAGUCUAAAGCAACAGGCAGCAAAUAUUUUCUUAAAGGGCCAGAGAAUAAAAGUGUUGGCUCACAGGCCAUGGGGUGUCUGUGGCGACCACCCAACUCCGCUUUGGAAGUAGCACCACAGCUACCAUAGACAAUAGGAAAAUGAUGGCUGUGGUUGCGUUCUAUUACAACUUUAGGUACUGACAGGCGAUGCACUGGAAUUGGCCCACAGGGUCUUAUUUGGUCAACCCCUGCUCUGGUGUAAAGAGGGAUGUGUUCCCGUGGUCAUCCCUAGGGAAUGAGUGGUGCAAACACUGGUCCUCUGUUAUUCUGCUGGACAGUGAGAUGGUGAUGGGAGACCCCUCAUCAUCAGUGGCAGGGCCCCAUCCAUUGUCUGGUAAUGCCAAAGCCAGAGAUGUGAGAGAGACUUUACAGUGGUAGAGGACUUGUUGACCCAGAUGGGCCGAUGCCUUGUUUCUGGGAAGCCACACCUCUGUCUAUGCAUUAAAGACUUCCAGGAGAACACCCCAGCACAGUGCAACCCAGAGCUGCCCCCUCAUAGCCAGCACACACAGAAGAGGAAGCGGGCAGUGGCUGUGUGUUGUCUCUGAUGCAAGCUUGCUCUGUGAAAGCCUGUUUCCUCACUGAUGGAAGGAAGCGUAGGGAUGAAAUAGAUGAUAGAGAUAAAAGAGCUUGGAUCAGUGCUUCUCAGUUGAGUUUGCAUGACGUCGUGGAGCUCAGCAUCCACGUGAAACUGUUGCAAGGAAAUGAUGUCAGUGUGCAAACAUCUUCGGGUCACAAUCGUCCCUUAAGCACGGCAGGCAUCAACCUUACCUCCAUCAGUGUUAGAGAGGCACGUUUCAUUUCCUCACUUCUGCCGUGAUGCAUGGUUGAUAGCUCUUUCUUGGUAUGUGGAGAAGUUUGCUUUGAAGAUGAUUCUGGCAAUUUUGUGAUGACCUCCCAUCCCAAUGGUUACACUAUUUCUGUGUCCACUCCAUUCUCUUCCUGAUACCAGGCAAGUGCUUGGGGGUAGGAAAUGAGUCCUGCCCUGCCUCAGUCUUUGACCAAGAAACGGCAAAGGUCUGCAGUCAAUUAGAGACUUGGAAGGAAGCCAUGGCUGGGGUAUGAAAUACACAGUGAGGGCCGCAUAUGUGCAGACACCCUGAGUAUAGGCUGUGAUACACAGGCUAUGGCCAUUGGUACAUUUUUCAUCUUGUGCAAGAGUCUACAGUGUGGCCCAGAAGCCAGCAGGUUCUAAUGAAGAAGGGAGGUGAAGGUAGGAAAAUGGCAUAGGAAGACAACCACAAAAUCCCAAUCUGCCGAGUGUGUGGGAGUGCAGGCUGUACCCAGCCAGCACAAGAAGGCAAUUGGCUUGAGGGUGUGGGAGACCUGGGGCAUCUCCACUGCAAGAUCUUUUUGUCUCUGUUGCUGCCUUACUUUAUUCAAAGACAAAUGUGCUCUCAUACCUCUUCCUUCUCUUUUUUGUGAGCUGAUUCUCACAUGGAUUGGCCUCAGAGACUAUGGAUAAAGCACACCUUUGCAUUCACCUCCUUUGCCCAAUUGGAUAAUUUACAGAUUAGCUAUUGACCUCUAUGGUCUGGCCUGCUCUCAUUUGUACUGUGUGUCCGGGGCCUGACAUUAGACCCCAGGAGGGAGGACCAUUUGGCCUGCCUUGAAGUCCAAGGGCAGAACCUUGUGAGUUAAUGCAAAUCACCGCCCUGUUCUGCCCCUGCUGGCUGCCUCACAACCUGCUGCAGAGCUUUUCUGUUUGACUCUGGAGGGACAAACACAGGCGAUGUCCCCUAGGAUCUCUUGCAGAAAUCAGCACCUGGAGUGGGCUCUCCCCAGCCCUCAUCCUGAGCCCUGCUGUGUGCACUGUGUCUGAUGGAGAGGCAGCCUCUCUGGAUGGCAGCUCUCUCCAUAUUCCAAAGGCAUUCUUCUCCUGUUCUCCUUCCCUCUUUUUAAAUUAAAUGGGAAUGCCACUGACGUGAUGUCGUUUGCACUGCAGGAUGACAGAACUGUUGUGUGAAUACCAUUGUAUUUGCCAAAUGGUCCACUCGUCAUUUCAGAACAAACAAAUGGAUGGUGUCUGUAAGUCGGCAAACACUGGUGACAUUUAGCCUUGUUUAUGUUCCUUUCCUUUUGCUGCAUAUUUUUGGCUCCAAAAGCUACUGGCUGAAUCAACAGGGCCUCUGAAUCAGGAGAGAAGUCUGGUAGCAUUAAUUUUAGUUGCUAUGUCCAUAUUCUCUUCAGACUGCAUGAAUCCUACUGCUCAGGACCAAGUCUAGGUGAGAGGAGAGGGCAAUCAACCUCUUUGGUUUCGGAUGUUGUGUGCAAAGCCCAGGGUUCAAAUAAGCAGUAAUUAUCUCCUAUUACUUAGUGCUGAUCAACAGCACCUCUACGUCUAAUUGCCAACCUGCCCUAAUCAUGUUGACUAUUCUUGCUUUAGCCAGAGACAGAAGGACCAAAUUUUAUAAAUAACACUUUAUUGUCAUUAUUCCAUUAAACGAUUAGGGGAUGUGGCCCUGCCCUUGCUUUCAAAUGCCUCUAGCCCUGAUGGUUUCUGGAUUAUUUAAUAAAUCUGCACAUUUUCUUGCAGGUAAGUGACACUCCCUGUCCUAGUCGGUCUAUCUGGACUUGCCCUUGUCUGUUCGUGGUCCUCGGUGGUUAUCUGCAGCUUGUUAAUCGUGUAAAGUCAAGAGAAGAAUGUAUACACAUAUGUGUGUUGAAUAAUUACUAUUGGCAUAGGUAUGUGUAUACACACGGUGCACCAAUCUACAGUAUAUAUAGCAGAGAAUCAGAGGCUAAAAAUAUUACCCCAUAUGUUCCAGUAUUAGUCAUGGAUUGCAAAGGCUUAGUAACUUGAGCAGGAGAGAAAACUCCCUCAAAGUCAUAAAUCCUGAGUGACAACUGCUGCUGGAUGACAGAUCCCUUCACCUGUGGACAACCUGGCUGGGGGUGGGGGGCUGUUCCACCAGCUCACCUGAGCAUGUAGAGGUGGGUCCUGCAGUGGUCUCGUGGGUAUUACUGCUUGUGUCUGAUUGUCCUGUAUUUUGUAACACUUUAGAAGAAUACAGAAAAGUGCAGUAAUUCUCUUUCUCCAUAGUAUUUAAGCAGAAAUAUUGCUAGUUUAAUAUUGUGUCAGGUCGUCCUAUUAACCAGGAGCAGAUGACAGUAAAAUUUCAGUGAAUAGCACCUUGACAUCUACAACUUAAAAAUGGUGAUUGAAGCAAAAUAUGUAAACUUGUACGGGGUGAUCGUGUGCUUUGGAACAGAGUAUUGUUGAAGUAAUUAGAAGAUAUAUUAAGGUGUUCCUGGUAAUGAAGGCAUGUAAGUUAUAAUAAUUGUAGCUUUCUGAAUAAGUGUCAAACUAUAUCUUUAAGUGUGCUGUAUGCUGAGUUACAAGUUAGGUCAUUUAUGAAUGGAAUGUAAAAUAAUACUAAAAAUGCUUCAAUAACUUAUCUUGGUAUUGCUAAUAAAAAAAAAAAGCUGUGAAACAUUA